ACAGCACGCUGCCACGCCGACGCAGACCCCUCUCUGCACGCCAGCCCGCCCGCACCCACCAUGGCCACAGUUCAGCAGCUGGAAGGAAGAUGGCGCCUGGUGGACAGCAAAGGCUUUGAUGAAUACAUGAAGGAGCUAGGAGUGGGAAUAGCUUUGCGAAAAAUGGGCGCAAUGGCCAAGCCAGAUUGUAUCAUCACUUGUGAUGGUAAAAACCUCACCAUAAAAACUGAGAGCACUUUGAAAACAACACAGUUUUCUUGUACCCUGGGAGAGAAGUUUGAAGAAACCACAGCUGAUGGCAGAAAAACUCAGACUGUCUGCAACUUUACAGAUGGUGCAUUGGUUCAGCAUCAGGAGUGGGAUGGGAAGGAAAGCACAAUAACAAGAAAAUUGAAAGAUGGGAAAUUAGUGGUGGAGUGUGUCAUGAACAAUGUCACCUGUACUCGGAUCUAUGAAAAAGUAGAAUAAAAAUUCCAUCAUCACUUUGGACAGGAGUUAAUUAAGAGAAUGACCAAGCUCAGUUCAAUGAGCAAAUCUCCAUACUGUUUCUUUCUUUUUUUUUUCAUUACUGUGUUCAAUUAUCUUUAUCAUAAACAUUUUACAUGCAGCUAUUUCAAAGUGUGUUGGAUUAAUUAGGAUCAUCCCUUUGGUUAAUAAAUAAAUGUGUUUGUGCUAA